AGGCUGAGACCGGUGCGCCGCGCGCUAGUGGCCGCUCUUCCGCGGGCUAGCGGGCGGUGGGGGCGCCAGCAGCGCGGAAGGCGGGCACGCGGGCCAUGGCUCCCUGGGCGGAGGCCGAGCACUCGGCGCUGAACCCGCUGCGCGCGGUGUGGCUCACGCUGACCGCCGCCUUCCUGCUGACCCUACUGCUGCAGCUCCUGCCGCCCGGCCUGCUCCCGGGCUGCGCGAUCUUCCAGGACCUGAUCCGCUAUGGGAAAACCAAGUGUGGGGAGCCGUCGCGCCCCGCCGCCUGCCGAGCCUUUGAUGUCCCCAAGAGAUAUUUUUCCCACUUUUAUAUCAUCUCAGUGCUGUGGAAUGGCUUCCUGCUUUGGUGCCUUACUCAAUCUCUGUUCCUGGGAGCACCUUUUCCAAGCUGGCUUCAUGGUUUGCUCAGAAUUCUCGGGGCGGCACAGUUCCAGGGAGGGGAGCUGGCACUGUCUGCAUUCUUAGUGCUAGUAUUUCUGUGGCUGCACAGCUUACGAAGACUCUUCGAGUGCCUCUACGUCAGUGUCUUCUCCAAUGUCAUGAUUCACGUCGUGCAGUACUGUUUUGGACUUGUCUAUUAUGUCCUUGUUGGCCUAACUGUGCUGAGCCAAGUGCCAAUGGAUGGCAGGAAUGCCUACAUAACAGGGAAAAAUCUAUUGAUGCAAGCACGGUGGUUCCAUAUUCUUGGGAUGAUGAUGUUCAUCUGGUCAUCUGCCCAUCAGUAUAAGUGCCAUGUUAUUCUCGGCAAUCUCAGGAAAAAUAAAGCAGGAGUGGUCAUUCACUGUAACCACAGGAUCCCAUUUGGAGACUGGUUUGAAUAUGUUUCUUCCCCUAACUACUUAGCAGAGCUGAUGAUCUACGUUUCCAUGGCCGUCACCUUUGGGUUCCACAACUUAACUUGGUGGCUAGUGGUGACAAAUGUCUUCUUUAAUCAGGCCCUGUCUGCCUUUCUCAGCCACCAAUUCUACAAAAGCAAAUUUGUCUCUUACCCGAAGCAUAGGAAAGCUUUCCUACCAUUUUUGUUUUAAGUUAACCUCAGUCAUGAAGAAUGCAAACCAGGUGAUGGUUUCAAUGCCUAAGGACAGUGAAGUCUGGAGCCCAAAGUACAGUUUCAGCAAAGCUGUUUGAAACUCUCCAUUCCAUUUCUAUACCCCACAAGUUUUCACUGAAUGAGCAUGGCAGUGCCACUCAAGAAAAUGAAUCUCCAAAGUAUCUUCAAAGAAUAAAUACUAAUGGCAGAUCUGCGAUUUCUGGGUCCACUUUCUGAGAUGCUUUCUAAAACCAACCAACUGAUAAAAAGUAGAUGAGACUUCUCCAAGCUGCUUCACAAGCAAACUAACCGAAAAACCGAAAAUAUACAAACAGCUUCACACACACACACACACACACACACACACACACACACACACAAAGGAAGAUCAUCAAUGGCUGCGGUAGCCUAGUAGGAAUGGACUAUAUAAUAAUAUAGCAGGUGCUCAAUAACUGUUUGUUGCAUUUCAGUAAAAGCAGAAUAACCUUUCAAAAUAAUAACAGGCUGGGUGCAAUGGCUCACACCUGUUAAUCCCAGCACUUCGGGAGGCCAAGGUGGGCAGUUCGCUUGGGCCCAAGAGUUCGAGACCAGCCUGGGCAACAUGGUGAAACCCUAUCUCCGUGAAAAAAUAUGAAAAUUAGCCAAGAGUGGUGGCACAUGCCUGUAGUCCCAGAUACUUGGGAGUGGGCUGAGAUGGGAGAAUCGCUUGAGCCCAGGAGGUCAAGGGUACAGUGAGCCGAGGUCAUGCCACUGCACUCCAGCCUGGCCUGGGCAACAGAGCAAGACCCUGUCUCAAAAUAAUAAUAAUAUAUAAUUUUACACCAAAAGUUUCAGGAAAAAACGAGUUUGUUGGAGUUAGUUUAUACUUUCACAUAUCACCACAAAGAUCUCCAGUUAAAUAACUAUCAAUAUCCAUUUCCAUUCAUCUCCCCCUCAAAUCAUAGCCUAACAGAACACUUUGAAAGCUCUUUUAUUUAAUAUUUUUUUACAUCCUUUGAAGGGAGUGCUUCAAAAAUGAAAGCAUCAGAAGAUAAAAUAUUUUUAUAUUUAUGCAUAGCAAGCCUUCGUGAACGGAAGUGACACACUCUGGAUUGAAUAAUACUGUAGCCUCAUUCAUAUGUAGUUAUUCAAAUUGGAUUAAUGUCUGUGUGAGUUUAUUUGAACUAGCAGAAAGUAUCUGAAGAUAUUCAGGAAUAAAGUUUAUACUUAAAAUAGCUUAUGUUAAAGAAAAUACCUGUGAUUAAUUCAGAGGGAAAUAAAUGCAUGGUAUAAAAGAAAACCAAAAACUUAAAAAAUAAUACUAUAGCCUGAGCAACACAUUAAAACUGCACACUUGUGCAGCGUAAGAUUCUCUGGCUUAUUGGCUGAGGUGUUAAGUUUAUUCCUUUUAUGAAGAUGUCCUAUUACAGUCAGCUAAGCACUAAAGCUUUGCAUUUAUAUGUACUUUGCUAUGGGGGAAAGAACCUUAUGAUUAAUAAGACACAUAUCAAAUGCAUAGUCAAUCAUUCCCACCCCCAUCCCUGGAGCUGUAACCCAAAACUGUUAAACUAAGAUUCCUUUGUUUUUUUUGUUUUUUUGAGAUGGAGUCUCACUCUGUCGCCCAGACUGGAGUGCAGUGGUGGGAUCCUGGCUCACUGCAACCUCCGCCUUCUGGGUUCCAGCGAUUCUCCUCUGCCUCAGCCUCCCAAGUAGCUGGGAUUACAGGCACAUGCCACCAUGCCCAGGUAAUUGUUGUAUUUUUAGUAGAGAUAGAGUUUCACCAUGUUGGCCAGGCUGGUCUCAAACUCCUGACCUCAGGUGAUCCACCUGCUUCGGCCUCCCAAAGUGCUGGGAUUACAGGUGUAAGUCACUGCUCCCGGAUGCAUGUCAAGCACAUUGGAAAGUUCUUACAACAAUUCUGAUGGAGGAUUUUCUCUCCCAUCAACCAAACACCACUUAAGAUUAACCUGUGGCUCAGUCUACUUAAAUAAAUGCCAUAUUUAUUUUACUUAUCAUUUAGAAUUUGCCAUUCUCAGGAACAAAACUUUUUGUACAUUGGAAAUGGAAAACAUUGCAGUUUGGUCUUAAUUUCCACAUGAAUAUCAAGUGUAAUUUUUAAUAAAUUAUUUGGAGAAAAAUGUAUUUUAUUUUAGCAUGCAAUUUUAUGCCCAGGUUAGACUAGAGAUUUGGCUGAUGUUCUGGAAUCUCAUUGUACUCUUAAGUAAAAUAACGAGCAUCCCAUGACGCACCCUGUCAGGGGUUGUGAGAAAGCUGCAGUGUCCAGUUUCCCACCCCUGUUUCCUGCUGUCUCUCUCCCACUCAUCCCUGUUUCUUACUCAUCCCUUUUCCUUCUUUGCCCAAACAUCAUAUUUCUAGGCAAAGAUAAGAGAGGAGAUAGUGAUGUCCUGAAAGGGGUUCAGAACAACGUAGCAUGGCCUUUGGUGAAAGCGUCACCGAUGGGAAAUAAUUGAGAAUUGUGCAGUGCUUGCAGCGUCAGAAUCAGCACUGUUUUUUGUGUUGGUGAAAAUAUUCCAUGUGCGUAAAGGGAGAGCAUCAGGGACUUUGCAAAUUCUUCACAAGGACCCAGAAAUAGCUUAAAGAUUCAUGGUUUUCCUGUUGGCUUAAAUAGCCUUAAUCUUUCAUUUUCUACUACCAUUAAGUCGGGGAAAUGACAUUGAACUACCUCAUUAGCAGCCUUCCCUUGAUUAACUACUGACUAAAAGUGUGCUGAAAAUGGCCUUUGUUUUUGUGAAGCUCAUCCUAUACACUAACAUUUGCUUAACCAUGGAUUAUUUUGUCUCUACAAAGCUGUGCCCUGUAUUCGAUUUUUACUUCAAUGAGUGGUUAUUGCUAGAAUUCCUACAAAAAAAAAAAAAACCGUUGCAGAUAUUUUUGUAUGUAGCUUAAUAGAUAUUUAGUUUAAGGAGACUGCAACAUUUGCAUAAGGUGCCUAAAAACUCAAGAACCAUUGAUAAGUGAGAUCACUCAAAAUGAGCUGAUAUAUUAAAGAAGACCUUAAAACAGUAAA